ACUGUCUCUAGCAGUGGGUGAAGGCCUGUGAGUGAGGAAUGCCUCUCACCAGCUGUGCCUGAGCUGCAGCACUCCAGCCACUGCUGUCUCCUUAGCUGCUCACAUAUGGAUACUUUCACAGUUCAGGAUUCCACUGCAAUGAGCUGGUGGAGGAAUAAUUUCUGGAUCAUCUUAGCUGUGGCCAUCAUCGUUGUCUCUGUGGGUCUGGGCCUCAUCCUGUACUGUGUCUGUAAGUGGCAGCUUAGACGAGGCAAGAAAUGGGAAAUUGCCAAGCCCCUGAAACACAAGCAAGUAGAUGAAGAAAAGAUGUAUGAGAAUGUUCUUAAUGAGUCGCCAGUUCAAUUACCGCCUCUGCCACCGAGGAAUUGGCCUUCUCUAGAAGACUCUUCCCCACAGGAAGCCCCAAGUCAGCCGCCCGCUACAUACUCACUGGUAAAUAAAGUUAAAAAUAAGAAGACUGUUUCCAUCCCAAGCUACAUUGAGCCUGAAGAUGACUAUGACGAUGUUGAAAUCCCUGCAAAUACUGAAAAAGCAUCAUUUUGAAACAGCCAUUUCUUCUUUUUGGCAAAACUGAAGAGGGUUCACACAACUUAUUUUAAAACAAUCAAGAAUGGUUGAACUUCAGUAGGUCUCUGGGCCCUGAAAGCCAGUGGUGAUUUUAUGAAGCUCUAUAAGAUAAAGCACUUCCCAAACCUUAGAUGAAGACACCCCUGCGAUCGGAUGACUGCAGCCAGAGGAGACACAUGGGUGCUCGGCUCUGAGGACUUAGAGGGGUCAGCCUUGUGCUGUUGAGGAAACUUUCCAUGGGAAGGACCACGGGGCUCCAUGGCUCCCACCUGUGGGAAACUACUCAUUUCUUGGCAUUCUUUCCCCCUUCAUUCCCUUUGGUUUGCAUGGUUCUGAGUGAUAUUAAAUCUCAGCAUUUGGUUGUGCAGACCCUCCCAGGCUCCCAUCCCCAGCAAGGCCCUCACCAAGCAUGCUGGUCUUUACCCUCUCACCCCACCCACCUCCUGCACUGUGAGGCUGUGGGUGAGUUACAGCUGAGUGCUCUCGUGCCCAGGUUCCCACACCACAUCUCGCGAGUUUGCAAGGGCAGGGAGUACCUUUUGUUCUCGUGAACCCUCCCCACCUAGACACCCUGCAAACCCCAGUGCCUUUAUAUGAUGUAGGCCAAAUUGACCAUAGAGAUUUGAGUUUUCACCUAGGUUUUCUCCCCGUGCUUGCAAGUUGUACUGUAACAAUGGACAAAGGACAAAAGUUACCUUCUGAUUUACACCUAGAAGCAUCAUUUUGCAAUAGGUGUGUUGGGGGUGCUACAGGAAAAAUACAUUUCCCCCAGGACAAAUCAUGGGGAACAGGAAAGAAAAGGGGCAUGUAACAAUGGCAUAUACAAGAUGAGAGUUCAGGGGGCUUAAUAUCCCCUGUCCAUCAUUUUCAUCAGUACUUACUCGAGUUCUAGGAAAACAGCCUCAAGCCCCUUCCUUCCAGAUCACUGUCCCUGGGCAUCUGGGAGGAGGCAGAAGGUCCACUGUGAUGUGCUGCAGCCAAUGAGAUGGGCCAGGGACAUGGGCAGAUGUCUUGUUAAACAAGUGUCCUAAUGGGGUCAACAAGGCCCGAGUCAGCUUUAUAGGCUCUUAGACCUCAUCAAUUCCUUCUAGCUGAUCGCCAGAGCCCUAGGACUUGACUCAUUCUAACUAUACUCACAAGAUGCUGGUUUCUAAGUGACCUCUGGGAAAUCUGGCAAAUGAACAGCCUUGCAGAGAGAGCACUGUGAACCUGGAAAGGCCUGAGAGUGACUCAGAUUUCCCUCAAGAGAUGGGAAAAUGUGUUCCUCCCAUUUUCAAGCUUUCUCCCUCAAUCAACGCUGGAGCACUGGGGACCUGGGCUUCCUCCCUGGUUCUCUCUUUCCAGACUCUAUGAAGGCUUCCACCUUGCUAUUAAUACCUCCUUGGGAGGCCAAGGUGGGCGGAUCACCUGAGGUCGGGAGUUCGAGACCAGCCUGACCAACAUGGAGAAACCCCAUUUCUACUAAAAAUACAAAAUUAGUCAGGCAUGGUCGCGCAUGCCUGUAAUCCCAGCUACUUGGGAGGCUGAGGCAGAAGAAUCGCUUGAAACUGGGAGGCGGAGGUUGCGGUGAGCCGAGAACAUGCCAUUGCACUCCAGCCUGGACAACAAGAGUGAAACUCCAUCUAAAAAUAAAUAAAUAAAUAAAUAAAUAAACCCUCCUUAUGUUAGGCCAGUAGUUAUCUAACUAUGGCCUUAUGGGACUCUGGUAUCCCACCAGCCAAAGAGAGGACUCUUCCCAAAUUAUAGAACAAAAAUAAGCCAAAGGAUUGGAGUGUUUCAAACACAUGCUUUCGUCUUAUAAAUGUUCUGUAAACCCUCCAUGACUAUGACAAAAGUUAAAAACAAAUGCCAGACAAA